CUGCGCGCUCGGGCUGGCUCGGCGGCUGCGGCGGGCGGGCAGGCGGGCAGGCCGGCAGGCGGGUGCGCGGAGGGCUGGUGCCCCGCAGCAGGUGGGCGGGGUGCGGUUGGCGGCGGCGGCUGGGCCGGGGGCUGCCGGCUGCGCUCGGGCCGUGCGCGGCGGCCGUGCGGGCACGCCAUGGACUUCAACAUGAAGAAGCUGGCGUCGGACGCGGGCAUCUUCUUCACCCGGGCGGUGCAGUUCACGGAGGAGAAAUUUGGCCAGGCUGAGAAGACUGAGCUUGAUGCCCACUUUGAAAACCUUCUGGCCCGGGCAGACAGCACCAAGAACUGGACAGAGAAGAUCUUGAGGCAGACAGAGGUGCUGCUGCAGCCCAACCCCAGUGCCCGAGUGGAGGAGUUCCUGUAUGAGAAGCUGGACAGGAAGGUCCCCUCAAGGGUCACCAACGGGGAGCUGCUGGCUCAGUACAUGGCAGACGCGGCCAGUGAGCUGGGGCCGACCACCCCCUAUGGGAAGACACUGAUCAAGGUGGCAGAAGCUGAAAAGCAACUGGGAGCCGCGGAGAGGGAUUUUAUCCACACGGCCUCCAUCAGCUUCCUCACACCCUUGCGCAACUUCCUGGAGGGGGACUGGAAGACCAUCUCGAAGGAGAGGCGGCUCCUCCAAAACCGGCGUCUGGACUUGGAUGCCUGCAAAGCGAGGCUGAAGAAGGCCAAGGCUGCAGAAGCCAAAGCCACGUGUGAGGGAGAUACGGUGCCUGACUUUCAGGAGACUAGACCUCGUAAUUACAUUCUCUCGGCCAGCGCCUCCGCGGGCACAGGCUCUAGGGUCCAGCUGUCCUCCUCUCCCCUCCCCUGCUGGCCACUCCUGCUGCCGUCUCCACAGCUCUGGAAUGAUGAAGUGGACAAGGCCGAGCAGGAGCUCCGCGUGGCCCAGACAGAGUUUGACCGGCAAGCAGAAGUGACCCGUCUCUUGCUGGAGGGAAUCAGUAGCACUCACGUGAACCACCUGCGCUGCCUCCACGAGUUCGUCAAGUCUCAGACAACCUACUACGCACAGUGCUACCGCCACAUGCUGGACUUGCAGAAGCAGCUGGGCAGCUCCCAGGGUGCCAUAUUUCCCGGCACCUUCGUGGGCACCACAGAGCCCGCCUCCCCACCCCUGAGCAGCACCUCACCCACCACUGCUGCGGCCACUAUGCCUGUGGUGCCCUCUGUGGCCAGCCUGGCCCCUCCGGGGGAGGCCUCGCUCUGCCUGGAAGAGGUGGCCCCCCCUGCCAGUGGGACCCGCAAAGCUCGGGUGCUCUAUGACUACGAGGCAGCCGACAGCAGUGAGCUGGCCCUGCUGGCUGAUGAGCUCAUCACUGUCUACAGCCUGCCUGGCAUGGACCCUGACUGGCUCAUUGGCGAGAGAGGCAACAAGAAGGGCAAGGUCCCUGUCACCUACUUGGAACUGCUCAGCUAGGCAGGUGCCCCCAUCCCCCCCGCAUUCUGGCCUAGGCAGGAGAGGAUGGGCGCAGCCCUGCCACUUAACUUGUUUGUUGGUGACACAGUUGUUCAGAGUGGGGAGAAUUCACCCCAUUCUGUCCCUGCCCCUAGUCACCUAGCUGUGAGGGUGCCUGAGGCUGAAUGGCUCCACCCCUCCCCCAGCCCUGCUUCUGACCUGUGGCUCUGGAGCCCCUGCCCCUGCCUGCAUCCCCGAGCACCCCACCCUCCAGGCUCCACUAAGGAGGGAGGGGCUGUCUGCAGCAGCUGCACUCAGCACCUAGGCCAGGGUGGGGCCGCCGCAGAUGGGCUCAGGAAGCCCCAGGUGCACUCAGCGAGAGCCCUGCCUUUCAGUUGCCAAAAGCUGCAUCAGGGGAAUGCGGCAAGGCACACAGGGCUCUGGCAGCCCCUGGGGACUGGGCGCUGCCCCUGGGAGGGGAGAGCCUGGCCAGGGCUGGUGUUGGGCCCGGAGCAGCAUCUUCCGGUGCUAUCCUCCCCUCCCACCCCUCACAGCUCAAGCCAAGUCCAGCGGCCGCAGUCUUCACCUCUCCACACUCACUUUUUAUCUGGUGUUUUUACUUCUGCCUGCGUUUGCUCUCUAGCCAAUAAACCGUCCUUGUGUGCGAGUCACCUGGGCUCCUGUCAGGGCCUGGCCCUGAGGGUGGUAAAGGGAAAGGUAGACUCACCCUCUGCCCCACUCUUCCACAGAGUGAGCAGGGGCCCUGUGGCUGCCCCGGCCCCCAGCUCUCUAGUUGGGAAGAAGUGCAGCCCUCCCUGUCUUCUGCGGGGCCUGUGCCUCUCAGAGGGCAGUGCUGUUCCUGGACAUGAAGCCGCACAAGGAACGUUUUAUUCCUAAGAAAAAGUUUCCUAAAUUUGGAUUGUGGAGCGGACUGUAGAAUGCGUCUGACAGUUCAGUUCAAGCACAAGAAGUGGGUAGCGGUCAGUGCUGUCUGCAGGUCGGGCGUUUCACCCAGCAUGUGCCCCCGUGCCAUGGGUUCUCAUGCCGUCCUCAGUGUCCACAUUUCACAGAUGAGAUCAGCAAGACAGUCAGCUCCUCAAGGGACCACAGUUGGCAAGUGGCCAAGCAGGGACUGAAGCCCAGGCAGCCUGAUUCUAGAAACCCUAAGUGAUGUCUGUGUUUUAGAUGGCCCCUAGCAGGACCUAGCAUUCUGACUUCAGUCCUGAGAAGGCCAACAGCCAGUAGGCCCCACUGUUGGGGCUUCUGAAGAGGGGAUCGGGGGAUGACGGGGGCACGGGGCUAUAAAUAGGAAGGCACAGAGCUUCAAGAAAGGCUCACCCAGGGAUGAGCUCAGCCCACUGGGCCAAUGAAAGCAGGGUCAAGGACAGGACCAGCGCAGGCCAAGGAAGGGAAUAUCUGACAGCGCCCACCCAGCCAAACCCUCAGCCCAAGGACAGGAAUGAGGAGAUGCUGGUGAACUAGCCAUCCAUCAGUACCUGCCUUCCCCCGAGGCUGCAGCCCCACUCCCAGGCGCCUGGCCAGGGGAGUUUUCUAGGUUCUGAGAGCCACGUUGUCAUCCCUGGGCUUUGAAGUUAAACAUCACACAGCUGUCUAUAAACAAGAUUUUAAUAUCUGUAUAAAUAGACCACAGAAUUACCAAAACUGCAAA